GAUUGCUACGUUCAGAUCAAACCUUGAACUUUUUUUUUUCUGGUGCCAGGAGCCUUCCUGUGCUCCCCAUUGCCUGCCAGAACCACCACCGUUUCCCAUGGUUACUCUACAGCAGCUUCACUGCCUGAAAAUGAAAACUGAACAAAGGGAUUAAAUUGUGAGAACAACUGUCAAUCUAUUAUAUAUUUGUACAAUCUGGUAUUAAAAUGCUUUCCCCAAAAGAUAUUCUGCGAAAAGAUCUGAAGUUGGUCCAUGGUUAUCCCAUGACCUGUGCUUUUGCAAGCAACUGGGAAAAAAUUGAACAGUUCCAUAGCAGACCAGAUGACAUUGUGAUAGCCACUUAUCCUAAAUCAGGUACUACUUGGGUUAGUGAAAUUAUAGACAUGAUUCUAAAUGAUGGAGAUAUUGAAAAAUGUAAGCGAGGUUUUAUUACUGAAAAAGUUCCAAUGUUGGAAAUGACUCUCCCUGGAUUAAGAACAUCAGGUAUAGAACAAUUGGAGAAGAAUCCAUCACCCCGGAUUGUGAAAACACAUCUACCGACUGAUCUUCUUCCUAAAUCUUUCUGGGAAAACAAUUGCAAGAUGAUUUAUCUGGCUCGUAAUGCCAAGGAUGUUUCAGUCUCAUAUUACCAUUUUGACUUAAUGAAUAAUUUACAGCCUUUUCCUGGUACCUGGGAAGAAUAUCUGGAGAAAUUCUUAACUGGAAAAGUGGCCUAUGGUUCCUGGUUUACUCAUGUUAAAAACUGGUGGAAGAAAAAGGAAGAACACCCAAUACUUUUUUUGUACUAUGAAGAUAUGAAAGAGAAUCCAAAGGAGGAAAUCAAGAAGAUCAUUAGAUUUCUAGAGAAGAACCUGAAUGAUGAGAUCUUGGAUAGGAUCAUCCAUCACACCUCAUUUGAAGUGAUGAAGGACAAUCCUUUGGUAAAUUAUACACAUCUACCAACUACAGUGAUGGAUCAUAGCAAAUCCCCUUUUAUGCGUAAAGGGACGGCUGGUGACUGGAAGAAUUACUUCACCGUGGCCCAAAAUGAGAAAUUUGAUGCUAUUUAUGAGACAGAAAUGUCCAAAACUGCACUUCAAUUCCGCACAGAGAUUUAAAGUGUCUAAAUCACACAUCUGAAGAAAUAAGAGAUUGUCUGUAGUUGAUUGAAACGAGGGCAGUUAUGAAUUGAUUUGGGCAAUCAAAUGAAUUUAUAAAGGAGAAUAAUAUGCUUUUAAUAUGUUGAUUCUUUUCAAUGUUAUUAAUCAGAUCCCAGUUUUGUUCCUUUGAUUCUGAGUUUCCAAAUUCUCUAAGGCUAAAGUUCAUUGUUAACUUUUUGUAACAAAGGAACAAUGUAACCACAGGCUCUUCCUGCCUUUUUCUACACUAGUACUGAUAAGAAAGAAGGGAUUUAUUUUACUUAAUCUCCCAUAUAUUAUGAUUUAGAAUUAAGUUCCCCUCCCUAGUACCAUGGUCCAAGAAAUGCUGUUUUCAUAAUGAGACUAUAUUUCCUAACUCUGCCCCAAUUUCCCUUUGCCGAAAAUUUGACCCAGGACACUGUGUUCCACUGCUGUCUACCGAGUUUCAAGUUGUUCUCUGAGUCAUAGCUCAUCUUCCUGCAGUGCCUCUAUUUGGAUAACAAAGUUCAUGUCCCCGAUCAUGUAGUUCAGAUUUUGGAAAUCUUUUUUCUAUAUCAUACCUAAUGUCUAAGUCUCCGAAAGGCAAACGCCUACAAUAGUCUCUGUAGGAUUGGUUACCUGGGAACUGGAGCUCUGUUCUGAAAAGCAGCCCUGAGGGCUGUGACCUACUUCUUAUGGGGAGUCCUCUUUUUCCCAACAGACCCGUUUGAACUUCAGAGAAAUCACCUACUGCUGUGUUCUGGUCACCAUUUGGGAACUUCAGUUACUUAAUCUUAUAUUUGGAUAGAUUUGGAUACCUUAAUAGCACCUUUAAUAUCCUAGACAUGAUCAUAACCUCUGCAAAAUAUUUCCCAAUCUGGUGCCCAAGGAAGACUCUCUAGGCUGAAUCUCCACUCUGCCCUCUUGACCCAAUGUUCCUUCUACUUAUUAUUACAUGCUUAUAUCUAUUUGUGUGGUCUCUGAUCUAUGUUUUCUUGGAACAUUUAUAUAUAUAUAUAUAUAUAUAUAUAUAUAUAUAUAUAUAUAUAUAUAUGUACAUUUUAUUAUUAUACUUUAAGUUCCAGGUUACAUGUGCACAAUGUGCAGGUUUGUUAUAUAUGCAUACAUGUGCCAUGUUGGUGUGCUGCAUCCAUUAACUCGUCAUUUACAUUAGGUAUACCUCCUAAUGCUAUCCUUCCCCCCUCCCUCCACCCCACAACAGGCCCCAGUGUGUGAUGUUACCUUUCCUGUGUCCAAGUGUUCUCAUCGUUCAAUUCCCACCAAUGACUAAGAACAUGAGGUGUUUGGUUUUUUUGUUCUUGCAAUAGUUUGCUGAAAAGUAUGGUUUCCAGCUUUAUCCAUGUCCCUACAAAGGACAUGAACUCAUCAUUUUUUAUGGCUGCACAGUAUUCUAUGGUGUAUAUGUGCCACAUUUUCUUAAUCCAGUCUAUCAUUGAUGGACAUUUGGGUUGGUUCCAAGUCUUUGCUAUUGUGAAUAGUGCCGCAAUAAAUAUACGUGUGCAUGUGUCUUUAUAGCAGCAUGAUUUAUAAUCCUUUGGGUAUAUACCCAGUAAUGGGAUGGCUGGGUCAAAUGGUAUUUCUAGUUCUAGAUCUCUGAGGAAUUGCCACACUGUCUUCCACAAUGGUUGAACUAGUUUACACUCCCACCAAAAGUGUAAAAGUGUUCCUAUUUCUCCACAUCCUUUCCAGCACCUGUUGUUUCCUGACUUUUUAAUGAUUGCCAUUCUAACUGGUGUGAGAUGGUAUCUCAUUGUGGUUUUGAUUUGCAUUUCCCUGAUGGCCAGUGAUGAUGAGCAUUUUUUCAUGUGUCUGUUGGCUGCAUAAAUGUCUUCUUUUGAGAAGUAUCUGUUCAUAUUCUUUGCACACUUGUUGAUGGGGUUGUUUUUUUUUUCUUGUAAAUUUGUUUGAGUUCUUUGUAGAUUCUGGAUAUUAGCCCUUUGUCAGAUGAGUAGAUUGCAAAAAUUUUCUCCCAUUCUGUAGGUUGCCUGUUCACGCUGAUGGUAGUUUCUUUUGCUGUGCAGAAGCUCUUUAGUUUAAUUAGAUCCCAUUUGUCAAUUUUGGCUUUUGUUGCCAUUGCUUUUGGUGUUUUAGACAUGAAGUCCUUGCCCAUGCCUAUGUCCUGAAUGAUAUUGCCUAGGUUUUCUUCUAGGGUUUUUAUGGUUUUAGGUCUUACAUUUAAGUCUUUAAUCCAUCUUGAAUUAAUUUUUGUAUAAGGUGUAAGGAAGGGAUCCAGGUUCUGCUUUCUACAUAUGGCUAGCCAGUUUUCCCAGCACCAUUUAUUAAAUAGGGAAUCCUUUCCCCAUUGCUUGUUUUCGUCAGGUUUGUCAAAGAUCAGAUAAUUGUAGAUGUGUAGUAUUAUUUCUGAGGGCUCUGUUCUGUUCCAUUGGUCUAUAUCUCUGUUUUGGUCCAGUACCAUGCUGUUUUGGUUACUGUAGCCUUGUAGUAUAGUUUGAAGUCAGGUAGUAUGAUGCUUCCAGCUUUGCUCUUUUGGCUUAGGAUUGACUUGGCAAUGCGGGCUCUUUUUUGGUUUCUUAUGAACUUUAAAGUAGUUUUUUCCAAUUCUGUGAAGAAAGUCAUUGGUAGCUUAAUGGGGAUGGCAUUGAAUCUAUAAAUGACCUUGGGCAGUAUGGCCAUUUUCAUGAUAUUGAUUCUUCCUAUCCAUGAGCAUGGAAUGUUCUUCUAUUUGUUUGUAUCCUCUUUUAUUUCAUUGAGCAGUGGUUUGUAGUUCUCCUUGAAGUGAUCCUUCACAUCCCUUGUAAGUUGGAUUCCUAGGUAUUUUAUUCUCUUUGAAGCAAUUGUGAAUGGGAGUUCACUCCUGAUUUGGCUCUCUGUCUGUUAUUGGUGUAUAAGAAUGCUUGUGAUUUUUGUACAUUGAUUUUGUAUCCUGAGACUUUGCUGAAGUUGCUUAUCAGCUUAAGGAGAUUUUGGGCUGAGACAAUGGGGUUUUCUACAUAUACAAUCAUGUCAUCUGCAAACAGGGACAAUUUGACUUCCUCUUCUCCUAAUUGAAUACCCUUUAUUUCUUUCUCCUGCCUGAUUGCCCUGGCCAGAACUUCCAACACUAUGUUGAAUAGGAGUGGUGAGAGACGGCAUCCCUGUCUUGUGCCAGUUUUCAAAGGGAAUGCUUCCAGGUUUUGCCCAUGCAGUAUGAUAUUGGCUGGUGGUUUGUCAUAGAGGGCUCUCCUUAUUUUGAGAUACAUUCCAUCAAUACCUAAUUUAUUGAGAGUUUUUAGCAUGAAGGCUGUUGAAUUUUGUCAAAGGCCUUUUCUGCAUCUAUUGAGAUAAUCAUGUGGUUUUUGUCUUUGGUUCUGUUUAUAUGCUGGAUUACAUUUAUUGAUUUGCAUAUGUUGAACCAGCCUUGAAUCCCAGGGAUGAAGCCCACUUGAUCAUGGUGGAUAAGCUUUUUGAUGUGCUGCUGGAUUCGGUUUGCCAGUAUUUUAUUGAGGAUUUUUGCAUCAAUGUUCAUCAGGGUUAUUGGUCUAAAAUUCUCUUUUUUUGUUGUGUCUCUGCCAGGCUUUGGUAUCAGGAUGAUGCUGGCCUCAUAAAAUGAGUUAGGGAGGAUUCCCUCCUUUUCUGUUCAUUGGAAUAGUUUCAGAAGGAAUGGUACCAGCUCCUCCUUGGACCUCUGGUAGAAUUCAGCUGUGAAUCUAUCUGGUCCUGGACUUCUUUUGGUUGGUAAGCUAUUAAUUAUUGCCUCUAUUUCAGAGCAUGUUAUUUUUCUAUUCAGAGAUUCAACUUCUUCCUGGUUUAUUCUUGGGAGGGUGUAUGUGUCGAGGAAUUUAUCCAUUUCUUCUAGAUUUUCUAGUUUAUUUGCGUAGAGGUGUUUUUAGUAUUCUCUGACGGUAGUUUGUAUUUCUGUGGGAUCAUCGGUGGUGAUAUCCCCUUUAUCUUUUUUUAUUGCAUCUAUUUGAUUCUUCUCUCUUUUCUUCUUUAUUAGUCUUGCUGGUGGUCUAUCAAUUUUGUUGAUCUUUUCGAAAAACCAGCUCCUGAAUUCACUGAUUUUUUGAAGGGGUUUUUGUGUCUUUGUCUCCUUCAGUUAUGCUCUGAUCUUAACUCCAGCUUGGCAUUAGAAGUAGUUGUUUAUAUCCCCAUGUGCAGCAAAGUCUUUUUCCUGAGAUCAUAUCACAUGUGCCAAGUUAUAUGCCAAGCCAUGGUUCUCAAGCUGAAGGUACAGUACCCUGGGCCCUUACUUGUUCUGAAAGGGGUGGGGGUGGUGGUUUUGGACAUACUGUUAGACUUUCUGAGCCACAACUGAGGUAGCUAUGGCUUAUCGUAUUUUGACUUCACAGGUGAAUCUCCGCUGUCAGCCAGGAAUAGCCAGGAAUAGCUAAAAUAGCUCCUUAAGCUGUAACAUUUCUCUUUUCCAACCCCAGCAAAGGAUUGGUCUAGUGGUAACAACAAACCUCAUAGAAGUAGUACACCUAUUAUUCUGGAGAUACUUGCUUCUAUAGAUUUAUUACAAUAUGUUUUAUAAAGUAUUUUAGAGUAUAUAAUUUGUGUUUAUGUUCCACAGAAACAUAUUUUAUAGGAGUUAAUCUUGACUAUCUAAAGGUAUUGUGAACUAGUUCCAGCUUUCUCCAAUACCCUUGUCCACGAGAAGUAAACUAAAUCAUGUAUCUAUUUCCUCUAUUAUCUUUAUUAAAUAAUAAGUUAAUGUGGCCUGAAUAUAUACGGAUUUCUGAUACUAUGGUCUAUUACUGAGGGAAAAAACACCACUAAACUAUCCUCUAAUCUGUGUAAUAGAUUAGCUACACUUUCUUCACUAGCAAGAUAAAAUAAUUUCCACAUUUUCUAGUUUUACUUUGUAGAAAUAACUCUCUGUAAUUGGACUGUAUUCAACGAAAACUUAGUAAGUUGUAAUUAUGCCUCAGGUAUGUUUCUAUGCACUGAGUGAAGAGUGGAGAUAAAAAUAGAAUUUAGAUUUUCCUUUACUUUUUAAAUAGGUUGUUGCCUCUUAUAUAUUUAUUCUAUGAUGCAAAUGUCACUAUCCUAAUUCCUCAGUUUAUGUUUAACAGCACACAGUGGCACUUCUAUGAUUCAAAUACAUUUGAUACCCUUUGAAAUCAAUCAGAAUACUGCAAAAUUAAUUUUUCUAAAACAAUGCUUUUAUCGUUAUUUCUCCUGUUGAAUCAUCAGUACAAUUUCCAAAUGAAAACACUUAAAAUAAUCUCAUAUUACAAUCUUUCUCUAACAGAACCAUGAUGUAAGGACAGUGAUAACAAAUAUCUGACAAUGAUAUGAUUAUUUCCUCAUCCAUGGAAAUUUUCCUUAAUAAACUAAAGGGCUAUUUUCUAAAAAGCCAAAGCAUUGCUUACAAGAACUUUUCAUCAUGACAUGGAUAGACACUCAGAUUCAUACAUUCAAAGGGAAGUGUCAUGUAUUCCCUUUCAAUCCACCCUAUUCUAUUGUGUUAUCUUCCUAAAUUAUUUUCUAUCUACAUUCUUCAUUCUCUUUCCCAUUGACCCUAUGUUCUGUGUGAUAAAAAUUGCGUCAUUGGAGGCUUUUGAAGGUUAAGUAUUAUGCCCCAUUUCACCAUUAAUCAACAUACAACCCUUCUCCAUAUUUUGUAAUUCCUUUCAUAUACAGAAAAAAAGAUACUAUAAUUUCUUCAAAAUGCUUGAUAUUAAUGAUAUAUGGGAAAACAAUUAUUUUGUGCAGCAAUCUUCAGAUAACUGGGAAAGGCCGGGGAAAAAGAGAGAUACUGGUGGUUAUCAAUGACCCAUGUAUAAAUUGUUUUUAUUAUGUAAGCUGUCUUCACAAAUGUCUUCUUAUGUAUGAUCAUUAGAACUGUUUUAUAUAUAUAUGUAAAAUUUCCACAUUAUCGAGACAUUACUUUCAGCAGUGAAGUAAUCCUUUUUUAACUGCCACUUAAUGAAUUCAAUAAAAUAUAAUUUAUUGUA